GAGUGUAAUAAAGUUUCUCCAGGGAGGCAGGGCCCGGGGAGAAAGUUGGAGCGGUAACCUAAGCUGGCAGUGGCGUGAUCCGGCACCAAAUCGGCCCGCGGUGCGGUGCGGAGACUCCAUGAGGCCCUGACGGAGUUUCGCUCUUAUCGUCCAGGCUGGAGUGCAAUGGUGCGAUCUCGGCUCACUGCAACCUCCGCCUCCUGAGUUCAAGUGAUUCUCCUGCCUCAGCCUCCUGAGUAGCUGGGAUUACAGGCGCCCACCACCACGCCCGGCUAAUUUUUGUAUUUUUAGUAGAGACGGGGUUUCCCCAUGUUGGCUAGGCUAGCCUCGAACUCCUGACCUCAGGUGCUCCACCCUUAUCAGCCUCCUUAAGUGUUAGGAUUACAGGCGUUAGCCACUGCGCCCGUCCCCGUUUUCCUCUUUCUUAACCUCCUCCAAGGGUAGAACUAUUUGAAAGGGCUGAACGUGGGGUUUGGCACGAGAGGGAGAGAGAGACUUGCCCUCAGACUCCCAGCCUCACUUCCUGGCUUUCCCUUCCCAGGACCAACCUCAUCCCAGAAGUAGCUCUAGGCCUUCCUAGACAUAAGUGGAUAAGACCAUGGAUUUGUUGGUGUGUGGCAUGUGGGUGUGACAUGAGCAAAAGUUUUCUACUACCAGAAGAACGGUAGUUUGGAGUGGGGGUAGAUAAUAGUGCUCUUUUUGUUGUUUGAUUUUUUUUUUUUUAAGGGACAGUUCAGUCGCUACUUCUCUGUCUCUUCCCCUCCCCCUAACCAGAGUUCUUGUCUGGGCAUUCCUCCUGGCCCCGUUUGCCCAGCCUUCCCUGCUGGAAACAUUCCUGAGGCUUUCGCCAUUUCCUGCCACUUCCCGCCCCUGUCCCCUCCUCCCAGUUGGGCUGCGAAGCCACACACAGCUUUUCCCCUACACCCAAUCACCUGGACUUCCAGUAGGCAAUCUCCUUUCUCCCUAUGUAAAUUUCAAGAGUCAUACGUCUUUCUUUUCUUCCGAACGCCCACACCCGUUGGUCCUUCCCUGGCUCUGGAUACUGUAGGCUCCCACAGAACAUCAUCUCUACAGAUGAGGGACAUCCUAGUGUGUGUUUGUGUGUUUUGGGGGUGUGAGGCUAUGGUGGAAUCCUUUCCUCAUUCUCUCUAUGCCCGAGAGCUGGCUGGAAAUGAAGUGAUAAAAUUCCUUCUCAGGAUUGGCUGGCAGAGUGACAAAGCUCUUCUGGAAUGAGCACUAAGGGGAGAUGUAAGAGUUAAGCACAGCAUCUAACACACUUCAAGUGUUAAUGUUGUUAAUCAGGAUAAUUAUCUAUCUAUAUUUUAAUUCUCUGAAGUAAAUCUAAGGGUAAUUCCAAGGUGAGCUGGGGGGAAUACGUAUUUUUUUUUUUUUGAGACGGAGUUUUGCUCUUGUCACCUAGGCUGGAGUGCAAUGGCUCGAUCUCGGCUCACUGCAACCUCCGCCUCCUGGGUUCGAGCGAUUCUCCUGCCUCAGCCUCCUGAGCUGGGAUUACAGGUGCCCGCCACCACGCCCAGCUAAUUUUUGUAUUUUUAGUAGAGACAGGGUUUCACCAUGUUGACCAGGCUGGUCUCGAACUCCUGACUUCAGGUGAUCCACCCGCCUCAGCCUCCCAAAGUGCUGGUAUCACAGGUGUGAGCCACCGCGCCCGGUAGGAAUACGUAUCUUUGUUUUUUUUUUUUUGGUCACUUUCCAGCUUUGCCUGUGGCAUUCUCCGGAAGAGCAGUGGCAGGAAGCCGUGGGUGGCAGGAAUGGGUUUGGGACUGUUCCCUGUGUCCAGCUUCAACCCAUCUUCUCCUGACACCCCUUUCUCCUGUACUUAUUUUUCUCCUGUCCUUAUUGACGCAGAUGUGUCUUCUGAUCUCUCUGUCCCUUCCUGGCCUGUAGUUUCUACUUCUCUUGGAGAACUGUUUCUUCCACCUCCUCCAGCCAGGCUCCUUCCCUGGUGUGAAGGAUGCUGUGCUCUUUGGUGGGGCUUAGGGCCCUGUAAGAGGAGGGAUGUGAAUUGGGGUGGUUUGGAGUGGGAGUGGGGACCUGAUUGCCUCAUUCUCACCCUUGACAGUGUGCUGUGUUAACAAGCCCUGUGGAAAGGGGAGACAGGACAGUGCUUGGCUAUGAGCCAUCGGUCUUGGUGUGGUAGAUGGCAUACGUAGAGAACAAGCCGUGACCAGCAUGUCCUCUUGUUCCCUUCUUGCCUGGUAGCUUCCUGAUGUAUCAUCCAGGUUGAACUUUAUUCCCCUUUUUUCACCAGCUUUGCUCUUCCUCUUGGCCCUGCUCUGCAUCCAUUGGGACCACUUACUUCCCAUCCCCACUUCGCUAGCUCCAGUCCACAGCUGCUGUAGCAGAGGAUGCUAAUGGCCCAGGCUUACUGUAUGGGGUAGCGGUUGGGGGUGGCCUGGGCUGGGGCCAGCCAGCUUUCGGGCAUAGAGAGGGUGGGGGAAUUCGAGUGUCCAACCAGGACAGGAAGGGAAAUGCUGAGCUCUGAGAUCUCCUCCCUUUUCCACCCCCAGCUGCCUCUGUUUCCUCCCUCAUUCCCCUGUACUCCUGCCUGGCUUCCUGCCCCCUUUGGCCUGCGUGUGUCCGGUUUUGAGUGACCCAGACCUCCUAUCUCCUUCCUUUCCGUCCCACUCUUCCAUCCUUCCCUCCCACCCCCACUUUACUUCUCCCCAGAUUACUAGUUGUUUGUAUAGGGCAGGGGAGAGGGGCUUGGAUAGCCCUACCCCCUGCUCCAGUUCGAGGUUGGGGCGGGGUGGGGGCUCAGCCCCUCUGAGCCUGUGAGUCAGCACUGUCCUCACGAUUGGUCUCUCCCCUUAGCUCCCCGCCCCUGGGGAGGAGCCAGAAGCGCUGGGUCCAGCCUGUUCUCUUCUCAGCCAGAGAAGAGGCUCCACGUUGGGCGGGGAUGGGGCCUGAAACUGUCUGGGUCUGAGCUGGGGAGCGGAAGCCACUUGUCCCUCUCCCUCCCCAGGACUUCUGUGACUCCUGGGCCACAGAGGUCCAACCAGGCUAAGGGCCUGGGGAUACCCCCUGCCUGGCCCCCUUGCCCAAACUGGCAGGGGGGCCAGGCUGGGCAGCAGCCCCUCUUUCACCUCAACUAUGGAUCUCCUGCCCCCCAAGCCCAAGUACAAUCCACUCCGGAAUGAGUCUCUGUCAUCGCUGGAGGAAGGGGCUUCUGGGUCCACCCCCCCGGAGGAGCUGCCUUCCCCAUCAGCUUCAUCCCUGGGGCCCAUCCUGCCUCCUCUGCCUGGGGACGAUAGUCCCACUACCCUGUGCUCCUUCUUCCCCCGGAUGAGCAACCUGAGGCUGGCCAACCCGGCUGGGGGGCGCCCAGGGUCUAAGGGGGAGCCAGGAAGGGCAGCUGAUGAUGGGGAGGGGAUCGUAGGGGCAGCCAUGCCAGACUCAGGCCCCCUACCCCUCCUCCAGGACAUGAACAAGCUGAGUGGAGGCGGCGGGCGCAGGACUCGGGUGGAAGGGGGCCAGCUUGGGGGCGAGGAGUGGACCCGCCACGGGAGCUUUGUCAAUAAGCCCACGCGGGGCUGGCUGCAUCCCAACGACAAAGUCAUGGGACCCGGGGUUUCCUACUUGGUUCGGUACAUGGGUUGUGUGGAGGUCCUCCAGUCAAUGCGUGCCCUGGACUUCAACACCCGGACUCAGGUCACCAGGGAGGCCAUCAGUCUGGUGUGUGAGGCUGUGCCGGGUGCUAAGGGGGCGACAAGGAGGAGAAAGCCCUGUAGCCGCCCGCUCAGCUCUAUCCUGGGGAGGAGUAACCUGAAAUUUGCUGGAAUGCCAAUCACUCUCACCGUCUCCACCAGCAGCCUCAACCUCAUGGCCGCAGACUGCAAACAGAUCAUCGCCAACCACCACAUGCAAUCUAUCUCAUUUGCAUCCGGCGGGGAUCCGGACACAGCCGAGUAUGUCGCCUAUGUUGCCAAAGACCCUGUGAAUCAGAGAGCCUGCCACAUUCUGGAGUGUCCCGAAGGGCUUGCCCAGGAUGUCAUCAGCACCAUUGGCCAGGCCUUCGAGUUGCGCUUCAAACAAUACCUCAGGAACCCACCCAAACUGGUCACCCCUCAUGACAGGAUGGCUGGCUUUGAUGGCUCAGCAUGGGAUGAGGAGGAGGAAGAGCCACCUGACCAUCAGUACUAUAAUGACUUCCCGGGGAAGGAACCCCCCUUGGGGGGGGUGGUAGACAUGAGGCUUCGGGAAGGAGCCGCUCCAGGGGCUGCUCGACCCACUGCACCCAAUGCCCAGACCCCCAGCCACUUGGGAGCUACAUUGCCUGUAGGACAGCCUGUUGGGGGAGAUCCAGAAGUCCGCAAACAGAUGCCACCUCCACCACCCUGUCCAGGCAGAGAGCUUUUUGAUGAUCCCUCCUAUGUCAACGUCCAGAACCUAGACAAGGCCCGGCAAGCAGUGGGUGGUGCUGGGCCCCCCAAUCCUGCUAUCAAUGGCAGUGCACCCCGGGACCUGUUUGACAUGAAGCCCUUCGAAGAUGCUCUUCGCGUGCCUCCACCUCCCCAGUCGGUGUCCAUGGCUGAGCAGCUCCGAGGGGAGCCCUGGUUCCAUGGGAAGCUGAGCCGGCGGGAGGCUGAGGCACUGCUGCAGCUCAAUGGGGACUUCCUGGUACGGGAGAGCACGACCACACCUGGCCAGUAUGUGCUCACUGGCUUGCAGAGUGGGCAGCCUAAGCAUUUGCUACUGGUGGACCCUGAGGGUGUGGUUCGGACUAAGGAUCACCGCUUUGAAAGUGUCAGUCACCUUAUCAGCUACCACAUGGACAAUCACUUGCCCAUCAUCUCUGCGGGCAGCGAACUGUGUCUACAGCAACCUGUGGAGCGGAAACUGUGAUCUGCCCUAGCGCUCUCUUCCAGAAGAUGCCCUCCAAUCCUUUCCACCCUAUUCCCUAACUCUCGGGACCUCGUUUGGGAGUGUUCUGUGGGCUUGGCCUUGUGUCAGAGCUGGGAGUAGCAUGGACUCUGGGUUUCAUAUCCAGCUGAGUGAGAGGGUUUGAGUCAAAAGCCUGGGUGAGAAUCCUGCCUCUCCCCAAACAUUAAUCACCAAAGUAUUAAUGUACAGAGUGGCCCCUCACCUGGGCCUUUCCUGUGCCAACCUGAUGCCCCUUCCCCAAGAAGGUGAGUGCUUGUCAUGGAAAAUGUCCUGUGGUGACAGGCCCAGUGGAACAGUCACCCUUCUGGGCAAGGGGGAACAAAUCACACCUCUGGGCUUCAGGGUAUCCCAGACCCCUCUCAACACCCGCCCCCCCCAUGUUUAAACUUUGUGCCUUUGACCAUCUCUUAGGUCUAAUGAUAUUUUAUGCAAACAGUUCUUGGACCCCUGAAUUCAAUGACAGGGAUGCCAACACCUUCUUGGCUUCUGGGACCUGUGUUCUUGCUGAGCACCCUCUCCGGUUUGGGUUGGGAUAACAGAGGCAGGAGUGGCAGCUGUCCCCUCUCCCUGGGGAUAUGCAACCCUUAGAGAUUGCCCCAGAGCCCCACUCCCGGCCAGGCGGGAGAUGGACCCCUCCCUUGCUCAGUGCCUCCUGGCCGGGGCCCCUCACCCCAAGGGGUCUGUAUAUACAUUUCAUAAGGCCUGCCCUCCCAUGUUGCAUGCCUAUGUACUCUACGCCAAAGUGCAGCCCUUCCUCCUGAAGCCUCUGCCCUGCCUCCCUUUCUGGGAGGGCGGGGUGGGGGUGACUGAAUUUGGGCCUCUUGUACAGUUAACUCUCCCAGGUGGAUUUUGUGGAGGUGAGAAAAGGGGCAUUGAGACUAUAAAGCAGUAGACAAUCCCCACAUACCAUCUGUAGAGUUGGAACUGCAUUCUUUUAAAGUUUUAUAUGCAUAUAUUUUAGGGCUGUAGACUUACUUUCCUAUUUUCUUUUCCAUUGCUUAUUCUUGAGCACAAAAUGAUAAUCAAUUAUUACAUUUAUACAUCACCUUUUUGACUUUUCCAAGCCCUUUUACAGCUCUUGGCAUUUUCCUCGCCUAGGCCUGUGAGGUAACUGGGAUCGCACCUUUUAUACCAGAGACCUGAGGCAGAUGAAAUUUAUUUCCAUCUAGGACUAGAAAAACUUGGGUCUCUUACCGCGAGACUGAGAGGCAGAAGUCAGCCCGAAUGCCUGUCAGUUUCAUGGAGGGGAAACGCAAAACCUGCAGUUCCUGAGUACCUUCUACAGGCCCGGCCCAGCCUAGGCCCGGGGUGGCCACACCACAGCAAGCCGGCCCCCCCUCUUUUGGCCUUGUGGAUAAGGGAGAGUUGACCGUUUUCAUCCUGGCCUCCUUUUGCUGUUUGGAUGUUUCCACGGGUCUCACUUAUACCAAAGGGAAAACUCUUCAUUAAAGUCCGUAUUUCUUCUA